AUCUUUUGGUGCAGAAGGUGACGGGAAACAGGCCGCAGACCUGAACUUCCAACCGUAUGUAGGCGAGAAGCCGGUGCCGAUACUCCCACUAUCCCACAAUGUCCCACUGGGCCCCAGAGUGGAAGAGGGCGGAGGCUAAUCCAAGAGACCUUGGGGCCAGCUGGGAUGUCAGGGGCAGCAGAGGCAGUGGCUGGAGUGGCCCCUUCGGCCAUCAGGGACCGAGAGCAGCAGGCUCCCGUGAACCACCACUCUGCUUUAAAAUAAAGAACAAUAUGGUUGGUGUGGUCAUUGGUUACAGUGGAUCAAAAAUAAAAGAUCUACAACAUUCGACAAACACUAAAAUACAGAUCAUAAACGGGGAAUCUGAAGCAAAAGUCAGAAUUUUUGGCAAUAGGGAAAUGAAAGCAAAGGCCAAAGCGGCUAUAGAAACACUUAUUAGAAAACAAGAAAGCUACAACUCAGAAUCCAGUGUGGAUAAUGCUGCAUCCCAAACCCCUAUUGGAAGAAAUCUAGGCAGAAAUGACAUUGUUGGAGAAGCUGAGCCAUUGUCAAAUUGGGAUCGCAUUAGGGCAGCAGUCGUGGAGUGCGAAAAGAGAAAAUGGGCAGAUCUACCACCAGUUAAGAAAAACUUUUACAUAGAAUCCAAAGCAACAAGCUGCAUGUCUGAAAUGCAGGUGAUUAACUGGAGAAAGGAAAAUUUCAACAUAACGUGUGAUGACUUGAAAAGUGGUGAAAAGCGUCUCAUUCCAAAACCAACUUGCAGGUUUAAAGACGCUUUUCAGCAAUACCCUGAUCUUCUGAAAAGCAUAAUAAGGGUAGGGAUUGUAAAGCCAACGCCAAUUCAGUCACAGGCAUGGCCAAUUAUUCUACAAGGAAUAGAUCUUAUAGUAGUUGCACAAACCGGAACAGGGAAAACAUUGUCCUAUCUAAUGCCUGGGUUUAUUCAUCUUGAUUCUCAACCAAUAUCUAGAGAGCAAAGGAAUGGGCCUGGGAUGCUAGUCCUUACACCCACUAGAGAGUUGGCUCUUCACGUGGAAGCUGAAUGUUCAAAGUAUUCAUAUAAAGGUCUCAAAAGCAUUUGCAUAUAUGGUGGUAGAAACAGAAAUGGACAAAUAGAAGACAUUAGCAAAGGUGUAGAUAUCAUUAUUGCAACUCCUGGGAGGCUGAAUGACCUACAAAUGAAUAACUCUGUCAACCUAAGAAGCAUAACCUACUUGGUUAUAGAUGAGGCAGAUAAAAUGCUGGAUAUGGAAUUUGAACCCCAGAUAAGGAAGAUUUUAUUAGAUGUGCGCCCAGACCGACAGACUGUUAUGACAAGUGCAACUUGGCCAGAUACUGUACGUCAACUAGCACUUUCUUAUUUGAAAGAUCCUAUGAUUGUUUAUGUUGGUAAUCUGAAUCUAGUGGCUGUAAAUACAGUGAAGCAAAAUAUAAUUGUUACCACAGAAAAAGAAAAACGAGCUCUCACCCAAGAAUUCGUAGAGAACAUGUCACCCAACGACAAAGUCAUCAUGUUUGUCAGCCAAAAACAUAUUGCUGAUGACUUGUCAAGCGACUUCAAUAUCCAAGGCAUAUCUGCAGAAUCAUUACAUGGCAACAGUGAACAGAGUGAUCAAGAGCGAGCAGUAGAGGACUUUAAAAGCGGAAACAUAAAGAUACUGAUUACAACUGAUAUAGUAUCCCGAGGUCUUGAUCUUAAUGAUGUCACACAUGUAUAUAAUUAUGAUUUCCCAAGGAAUAUUGACGUAUAUGUACACAGAGUAGGGUACAUUGGACGGACAGGAAAGACUGGCACAUCAGUUACCCUCAUCACUCAGAGAGAUUCGAAAAUGGCCGGUGAAUUGAUUAAAAUUCUGGACAGAGCAAAUCAGAGUGUUCCGGAAGAUCUUGUAGUAAUGGCUGAGCAAUACAAGUUAAAUCAACAAAAGAGGCACAGAGAAACACGAUCAAGAAAACCUGGACAAAGACGCAAGGAGUUUUAUUUUUUAAGUUGAAAAGUUGUACCAGGCUACUGGAAGAUUCCAGGCAUGUUAAAGAUAUGCAGUAUUGAAUAUAUGUAAGGAAGUAUUGGAAACAUACUAGCCAUUUGAAGACAUAACUAAUUCUUAAAUAAUACUGCUAAACUUUCAAUAUUGUGUAUGCUCCUUAAUUUUAAAAAAGUCUCAAAAAUGAGAGAGUGAGAGACUGUGUGAAGAGAAAGUGAAUGUUACGUGUUGGUUAAAGUUUAAUUUCUCUUAAAAAUACUUUUAUUUUAGGUUUGGGGGUAUAUGUGAAGGUUUGUUAAAGAAACACGUGCCAUGGGGGUUUAUCAACUUUCAAUAUUGUGUAUGUUCCUUAAUUUUAGAAAAAGUCUCAAAAAUGAGAGAGAGACUAUGUGAAGAGAAGGUAAAUGUUAUGUGUUGGUUAAAGUUUAAUUUCUCCUAAAAAUACUUUUAUUUUAGGUUUGGGGGUAUUUGUGAAGGUUUGUUAAAGAAACACGUGUCAUGGGGGUUUAUCAACUUUCAAUAUUGUGUAUGCUCCUUAAUUUUAAAAAAGUCUCAAAAAUGAGAGAGUGAGAGACUAUGUGAAGAGAAAGUAAAUGUUACGUGUUGGUUAAAGUUUAAUUUCUCUUAAAAAUACUUUUAUUUUAGGUUUGGGGGUAUAUGUGAAGGUUUGUUAAAGAAACACGUGUCAUGGGGGUUUAUCAACUUUCAAUAUUGUGUAUGUUCCUUAAUUUUAAAAAAGUCUCAAAAAUGAGAGAGUGAGAGACUAUGUGAAGAGAAAGUAAAUGUUAUGUGUUGGUUAAAGUUUAAUUUCUCUUAAAAAUACUUUUAUUUUAGGUUUGGGGGUAUAUGUGAAGGUUUGUUAAAGAAACACGUGUCAUGGGGGUUUACUGUACAUAUUAUUUCGUCACCCAGGUAUUAAGACCAGUGCCCAAUAAUUAUCUUUUCUGCUCUUCUGCCUCCUUCCACCCUCCCCCAUCAGCUAGACCCCAGUGUCUGCUGUUUCCUUCUUUGCGUUCAUAAGUUCUCAUCGUUUGCUUCCCACUUAUAAGUGAGAACAUGUGGUAUUUGAGUUUCUGUUCUUGUGUUAAUUUUAUAGUCUACCAUGUCCAUUUGUCUUCUCUAAAACACUUGGUAGAAGACAACAAUGGUGCUUUUCUGGCUUUAAAAUAGUUGUACUAAAUUGAAGCAUAGCUUCAAGCUUAUCCAGUCAAAGUAUUCUCUUUUCCCCCGAGCAGUUGGUGCCACAACAGUUCUUAAAGUUAUUUCCACUAUCAUUCUCUACUUGUUUUAGUUCAUUAGAAAAUAAGUGCUAAAUUUUUUAGAAGAUUCCACAAUUCUAUUUUUAUCAGAAUGAUGUCACCAGCAGAGCAGGAUGUCUGACUCACUGGGAUUCAGGUCCUUGUAUGCAUUUUGUCACUAACCCUUGGUUAAAACUCUGAGGAAAUCACUUGCCUUCUCUAGGCCUCAAUUUCUCUACUCAUAAAAUGGGACAGUUUUAUUAAUUUAGAGGUCUCUUUUACCUCUAAAAUUCGGUGACAUUAUAACUAAAACUGUAUACCCCAGCCUUGUAUUAACACUUUUUUGUCUAAUCUAGGGGAAAUUGCAUCCUUGUAUAAUUGAAUAAAACAAUCCUUUUCAAUGACAA